UCAGGGAGGUGGAUGGGAGUCAGACUGUGAAGAAUCACCUAGGUCCUGCGUAGGACUUGAGUUUCACACUGUUGACACAACGAAGACAUGGAAUAUGUUUUAGAUCUUUCAGAGUCAGCUGACUCUAGUAAUGACAUGGUAUGUGGAUUGGAGGCAGGCAAGACUAGAGGCAGGUCGGCAAGGAAGGAGUCCAGUAGAGAUGAUGAGCACAUAACCCAGGGGAAACCCAGGAUGUGGCAGCCCAAUAUUGAGGAGUGAGAAUCAUUAGAACUCAGUGAUUGAUAUGUUUCUCAGGGCAGGGAAGGAAAGGGGACAUUUUAAACAAUGUCUUUAUAGUGAACCAGAUUCUGUCUCAGGUACAGCAGAAAUGUGGAAGGCCCACCUGUCUCGAGGAUAGUGGGGUCUGAGCAUCUCUCAGGGGUCUUCCUACCAAAGGCAAGACUUUGCAGCACCAGAGAGACUAACUUCCACUGCCUGUGCUUAACCAAAAGGGACUUCAGGCCAGGGAGGAGCUGCAAAGCCCCACACACAGCACCACAUGCGAGGGAAGAAGUCGGAACCUUAUCACAGGGCACAGACUUUGUAAGAGAUACAUAAAAGAAGAAAUUAACUCCCUGAUGGACCCUCAGCUUUUGGACUGAAGCAUUGGGGACUUGCUAAUGAGACUGAAAGAAAGUUGUUGUGGGUUGGGCUUUCCUAAUUCUGGAUUGAGACUGUAACUUACUUAGAGGCUGUGCUGAAAUUGACUCUAGUCAACAGGAAAGAGGAAAACUUGCUGAACAGAUACUGAAGUAUAAUCCCAACCCCUUCCUUCCACUGAGGAUUUGAGUUUGCUGAUGGUGUGAGGAAGAUCGUAAGGGAAGGGUUUGCUCCUUGAGGAAAUAAAUGGGUUAGAAUAAAGUGCUCCAGAAUUGUCCACUUCUGGGACCCACCCAGUUCAGGUGCAGGCUGAGACUAAUUCAAAUCAUUCUCAUCGGUUUACGAAAGCAGUACCUCUUAACAAGAUAGGAUCCAUCUGUUCUCGAGUCUCUACCUUUCAUAUGUGUGUGUAUAUAGAUGAGGUCUCGCUCUGUUGCCCAGGCUGGAGUACAGUGGCAUGAUCAUGGCUCACUGUAGCCUCAAACUCCUGGGCUCAGGUGAUCCUCCUACCUCAACCUCUGGAGUAGCUGGGAUUACAGGUGCAUGCCACCAUGCUCAGCUAAUUAAUUUUUUUGUAGACAUGAAGUCUUGCUAUGUUGCCCAGGCUGGUCUCAAACUCCUGGCCUCAAGCUAUCUCCAGACUCUGCCUCCCAAAGUGCUGGGAUUACAGACAUGAGCCAUUGCACCAGGCUGUAUCUGUACCUUUCUGUUCCUUCUUGAAAUUAGCAAGGGCUCUAUAUUUGUGGCAGUAAUGACCACCCUGAGGAGACCAUCCAACUCCUUUCUUCUCCAAAGGCCAGACGCCCCUGCAAGAAAGUAGGUAGAUAAACAGCGACUGUGCUUAAAGAUUCAAAACCCGUUUUCCCUGGUCCUAGGCAAGGAAAGGUAUUUGAGUGAAGACUAAGUUAGUGUUUGGCUCCCAGCACCUCCUGUUAGGUCUUUACUGCCCAGGAUGGCUGUGGAUAGCAUAAACUCUUGAGUAACCAGUGAGCGUUCUUGCUUCUCAGCUGCUGUUAUGAAGUUCAUCUUGAAAAUUGCUGCUUACCGCUAAAGCUAGGCACUGGGCUUCACUGCCCCACCCCCGGCCAGGCCUGCAGUUCUGUCUAAUGACUCCCUGCCAUUUCUGCUGGCAGCCCUACGUUGGCGGGAAGGUGUUUUUUUGUUGUUGUUGUCGUUUUGUUUUUCUUCAAGGUUUGGACAAUCCUAGAUUACUUGGUCUUUGAGUCCAGCUCUGGUUAGAACUUCUCAAAGGUAACCUGUUUUUCUCCAUUUCAAAACAUUUUUGAGGACCUUGAAAUUCAUUUCCAGAAAACAUCUGAGUAUUAACCAUCCUUUGCCUUAAUGGAGGCUGGUCAUUUCUCAUUGUGCCUCUGUACCCAGGACGUGCAGUGGACUUCUGAUGUCUUCUUGCCUUUGGAAGGCAUCUCAUCACUACCUCCAAGUUAUGGCCGCCUCUCCUCCUUUCACUGGGUUGUUAGUUCUUGUGCCUAAGUAGUGGAUCAAAUGUUCCAAAGUCCUCUUUAUCAUUUCUCCUAAGAUGCCCCAGAGGCCCUCAUCUGGAAUAGAAUUUCUGAAGGAGUUCCCUGCUGUCCCAGAGCUCUCCAGACAGCCUUGCACAGCAGAUCCACUGCAUGAUGCUUGCAAAAACCAAUGCCACCUAGGUUUUUAUUACUUGCGUGCCGUGUUUCUUUCUACCCUUAUUUGUCUAGACUAAACCAUUACUCCUGCUAGGAGAACUGUCUGGUCUCCUUUUAUUCAUCCUUCAGGUCUUGGCCAACCCCAGGGAACAUUCUGUUACCUUCCCAGCUUGGCCUCCUCUGAAUUUCUGUGGCAUUUACCUAGUUUAGCCCAUAAUUGCAUAUUGCUUUGUAUGCAGGUGUCACCAAGAUUCUAAGCACCUUUGGGGUAAAGGCCUGGUCUUAAACUGUUUUUAAUCCCCAUAGUAAUUGGUACUAAGUGGAUAAUAGUGGCCUCAUAAGUACUUUCAGUUUAUUUAAUUGAUAUGACUGGCUCCUAAUUGUGUUUAUCACUUAGAUAAAGGUGACUACCCAGCGGAGAGAUGGGAGAGAUCACCUGGAAAGUGUGCUCAGCCUAACAGGGCCCCUUUCCAUCAAAGCUGAGAGAAAAGCAAAGUGGAAACCACUGAAUCCCUAUUUUCAGCUUUCUUCUGGUGAUUUUGUUUAAUUGCAACAAUUUGCCGUGUUGUGACACUGAAAAACACUUAGGUGGAAGACUGAUCUUAACCACUAAAGUCAGGAAGAUUAUUAAGAUGGAAUAAAAUUCUGAAAAAUAUUGCUUUUAUGAACAAAAUUUUAAAAUAAUUAGCUACAAUGUUAUGAGGGUUGCUGAAGCUUUGGUGGGCACUCAGUGACCACCGUGUGCAGGUAACAGGAGCCCUGGACUGAGAGAAGAUGUGAGCUCUGCAAGGGACUUUUCCUGCAGUGUUGGUGGCUUGGCCCCAGAUUCUUACGCUGUUGUGUGGGCAGAAUCACAGGCCUGUCCCAGCCUUAGAGUGGUGCUGAGGCUCUGAUGAGAUAACAUCUGUGGGGGUGUUUUGUAAACCAUAAAUGCUAGGUGAAUUGUAAGGGGAGUUAGUUAUCAUAGCACUCUUAAGAAUUAAAUCCAGUAGGGUUUGAAUUACAGGAUCUCUUCUGAUCUGUUUUUCACCGAGAUCCAGUUCUUAGUGAAAGAGCCUAUAAUGACACUUUAUGUGGGAGAUUCAGGGAAGUGUUCACGAUGCAAUUCCAGUUUGUGAUAAUGGGCUGGUAAAGAGGAAGGAGGAAAUGCUAUUUAACUACCCUCUCCAGUUAUUGAGUGCAUCUUUUCAAACAGAUGAAAUUUUAUCCUGAUGAAAGAGGAAACCCUAGGUGAUCUAGUUCCUACGCUGUGAAUUUGAAUGGUCUUAAUCAAACAACCACAGACACAGGAAUGAGGGACUGUGCGACAUUUUGAAAUAUAAAUUAAGUAGGUGAUUGCUUUUCACUUCAACAAUAACAAGAGCAUACAUUUCUGGCAUCUCCGCCUCGUCUUCUGUGUUACCCUGAGCCUCUGUUCACAGGCCUGUCUUUAUCACCAGCCUCUCAAAUUCCACUGUAAGCAAAUGAUGCAUUUCUGAGGACUGACUUAAAGAAAUUUUGGGUUAUACUUAGUUCUGUGGUUAAAGAACAGACAUUUUCCAGAACUGUCUAAGAAAUGAAUUUGUACCAAAGGCGAGCAGUAAGUUAGUAAUAGGUCUAUCUUAGAGGGCAUAUAAGUAGAAUAAAUUCACUCCGCAGAUAUUCAAGUGUUUGCUUUGAGCAAAGUGUGUUUCUGAACAGUGGGGAUACAUCAGUAAACAGCGGCAACGACAGGAGCCCAGCCCUCUAGGAGCUCCCAUCCUAAUGGGAGCGCAGUAUGUAAACACGUAGUAGUUAAUGCUGUAAAGACAAAGGCAGGGUCGAGGUAGGUAGAGCAUGAUGGGGUGGGCACGGUUUCACAUAGGUGACCAGGAAGGGCCUCGCUGGUUGAAGGCCUGAGGGUUCCAAAGGAAAUGUUCCAGGUAUCCCAGAACUCAUUUCAGAUGGUGGGAAUAGUAAGUUCAAGGAUGCCGGGGUUUACCCAUUUCAGGAUUAGCAGAGCCCAGGGAGGCUGAUGGGGAUUGAGCGAGCGUAGUGAGGUUGGAUAUGGAGGCUGUGAAUCUGUCAGAGGCCUACUGUCAGGCCAUAGCAAGGCUGCCUCUGGCUUUUACACUGAAUGACGAACUGCUGGAAAAAUGUACAUUAUAAUAAUUUAAGAAUCUUAGCGUUUUAUAUUCAUUAUAUUUUGAGACAUUCUCCAUGCACAGAUUGUUACUAAUCAUUAAAUAAUAAUAAAAGUAAUGAAUGCAUGGUGCUAAGCACAAUCAACAAUAUUUGAAUACCAACUCUUUUUUUUAAUGGGACAAUUAUGUUAAUGAUAAAAAUUACAUUCCCAAAUUGCCAUAGUAGACUCAAGGCCUCUCUGAAUUAUCAAGUGAAAUGAAGGUUUCAAGGCCCAAAGACACGGGCCUUGGUCAGACCCCCUGUGGAACAGCUCGGAUUUACACAACCAGCAGUUCUUGGUCUGAAGAGGAAAGGUUGGGUCCGUGGCAUGGCUACAGGCACUAAGUUCACCACCCACUCUUAGUCCAGGUAACAGGGUAAAAGUAGUGAGGCUCAGGCUUCACUCCAGCCUGCUCUGGUGGUGAAGUUGGAGGGAGAAACCUGCAGCUGUGCCCAAGAGGACCGGCCCGUCUUCCAUAUAGGAAGUCCUGGAGGAAUCUGGGCUGAUUCACAUCUGCAGUGAGAUGAGGGCAUCUGGAGAGGGUAUGAAUGGGGGGCGUCCUAAUACUUUCAGAGCUUGAAUCCAUUUACUCCCUCAUUUUAUUGUCCAGAAUGUAAGGGACACACAAGAAGUUGUCUUGCCUAUGGAGAACAAGUUCUCACAGGCUGCGUGGCGCACAAGCUGUGUCUGUGGCCAUCUGCCAAGUCACAAAUGGCUUGGCCAUCACAGUGCUUUGCCCCAGUUGUAUUUACUGCAAUGGAAUUUUUAGCAGUGCACCAAGAACUCUCUUGUUCUUUCCCUUUUCUCUUUACCCCUCACCGUUUCUUCCCUUUUCCAACCCCAGUCUUACUCCUGGUUGUCAUGAUCAUACUAUGAUAGAUUUGGAAAGGACCUAAGAGAUGGGUCUGAAGCUCGGAGAGAUCAACUGACUCCCAGGCGUCAUCUCCUAGUAAAUAAAAAAUGGAGGAAAGGAGUAAGUAUCCUCACUCCCAGCUUGUGGGUCUUAAUCCUAAAAUUCUAAACUCAUCUGCUCUUCACACAUCACCCCAGAAUUUCUGUUCUUGACCUUAACCUCAGAGCCCAACCCAUCUCUUAUCCCAGGCACCUGAUCCUAUCCAUUUGCUGUAUUAAAAUCUCAGCUCCACGGCUGCAGGAGACCUGCAGUGAAUUCUUCACACUGGCUGUUGCUAAGAACACUCGAUGUGUUUCUGUUAGAAGUUAUUCUGUGUCUCAGUUGGGUACUAUUAAUACUAUCCUUCAGGCUCAUCGUGAGUUGAGUAGCUUUAUUAUGAGCUGUCCCACCACAAAAUAAUUAACCACCCUUUGUAAGAUUGUAUGUGAAAUUACCCUCCCAGUUCCAGAAAAGGGAGUUUUGUUUGGCCAGUUGGGAAGCUGUGUGUGCACAAUCAAAUGUGAGGGAGAGGUAGGAAUUGAGAAGGGCUCUUUCAUUAUCAAGGCCUUGCGGGUUUGCAAACGAUCCAGAAUUAGCAAGAAAAUGUAAACUCACAAUUAUUUCAGGUCCUGAGUCAUAUUAGGAAAGCAUAUUAAGAAGAUUGCCCUCUGAUUUAUAGACAAUGUGCUCUGUGGGCUGCAGAGAGGGCAGGGUUUGCUUCCUCCAUCCAGGCAGAGCGCGCACAGCCUGGACUUGUGGGCAGGCAGCCAGGGAUCAGCACCUCCAUAAAGCACCUCCCUGAUACAUGGCAUCUUCUAGCCAUUUUUCUAGCCAAAAAAGAGUUCUGACUCACUGAUGUGUCCAGGCUUCCAGACAUCCAUCAGCUCCUGCCUGGUUUCACUCUGAAUGUAGGAGCUUCACACUAAAUACAUCAGGAACUUCUUGGAAAAUGGGCUUGAGAUCAAAUAAAAACAAUUGAAAGCUGGCAGAAGUAGUGCCAUCUACAGAUUAGCAGGUGACAUAAAUUCACUGGACUAGAAUGAAAAUUCGAAUCUCUACAUGCAUACUCCAAAUGAGUAGGAAGAAUGUUUUGAAAGGACAUAAUUUUUUAAAGGGGGGAGAUGUUGGAACAAUAUUCUAAUGAAAAGAAAGACAGCAGCUAGAGAUGCUUCUGUACCAGCUUAGGUUGAAUAUAGACUCUAAUAAGGACGGUGUCAAAGAUCAAAGAAAAAUGUGAAUACAGCAUUGUAACCCUCUGAUGUGCAUUGUGAUCCGUUUUAGGGAUUGGCCUGGCAGCAUAAAGGCCCCUGCAUCAGUGUGUCUGUCCCAUUUCUAUUCAGUUUCCAGAUUUGGCUAAUUCCUUGGAUCAUCAGAUUUCUGGAGAAAUGUCUCUCUGAUCAAUUAAGAAUGACCCAAUUAAUACGAUGAGCCAUGGUGGUGCCACUGCACUCCAGCCUGGGUAACAGUGAGAUGCUAUCUUAAUAUAUGAAUGAAUGAAUAAGAAUAAGAAUUUGACAUUAUGUGCUCAAACAUCAAUAAACUCUUCUAAAUGAUAUACCUGUGAUUAGAAUAGCCUGCACUGCAUGUUUCAAGUGCUAGAACAAUUUAAUAAUUGGCUUUAUGGAACCAAGAAAACAAUCCCAGGUCUGAUCUGAGGUUAUUAUUAGCAGUCAUGGUCUUUUUAUUUUUUUUCUAAGCCACUAAAUUAAUUGCAUGACCGUAUGCAAUACCAUACCUUCUCUAGGCCUCCAUUUUUUAGAGUAAAGAAAAACCUUUAUGAAAAUACAUCCAAGUUUUUCCAAGUCUAAUGUUCUAGUUCUGAGAAGAGAUGUGUAGACCUGUUUUUAUCUUGCUUGAUAAUUAUAUAUCUAUAGAGAACAACCUUUAAUGUAAUUUUUUCCCUCCUCCUUUAUAAGGGUUUGUGGUUCUUUUUCUCUUUAAAAGACUGUAGUAAAGGUCCCUUGAGUAUCUCCCUUCUGAUGAUCAGGCUUAACCAACAUUUAUGUUUAGUAGGAUAUCAACAGUAUCUCAUCUCCAUAUUAGAGUGAUUUUUUAAAAUAAUGAUUUGAUGACCCUGGGCAAUUUAAACAGUAUAUUUCUGAGAGCUUUAUUUUGUAUUAUUUUUACUUUUAAUCAGAAAAACAUACCAUGUGAACAAAGUGUGGAGAUUCAAGAAUAGUUUCUUAAUAUUAUGCCCCAUUAAAAAUAAAGUUUUAUGAAGAUGGCAUCUCUGGGCCUAUAGUUUGUUUUUAAGUUUGAAAAACAGUGAUUUAACCCAGAUCAGUUUUUGAAAAAGUACGUGCCUUCUGUGUAUCAAAAAAAAAAUAACAGCAUAAAAUAAAAUUCUGUAGAGGCCGAACAUUAGUGUAGUUGGAGUAAUAAUGUGGUACCCCUCUCAGUUGUUCCAUGGGCUUAAACAGCUCAUCUGGUGGCUGUUCACAGCAAUCCAGCAAGUCUGGGUGUAUAUUUAGUUCUACCCAUUAAGUAGCUGGAAAUUAUCCUAACACUACACAAUUAAUAAGUGCGUAUUGUACCAAGAAUGCCAUGAGGUCUCUCCUGAGUCUCACUUUCCUCCUAAGGGCCAACUACUUUAAAAAGACAGGCUCUAAUUCUUCUCAUGGUGUGCUGCUGUAUAGCUCUUAAUUUGUGAGUUUUUAUAUGUAAAUGUCAUGACUGUGGUUUGUCAUCACAACACCCUCCAUCAGCCAGGGGUACAGAGAGAGAAGAUGGUGAAGCUAGGAGGAGCAGUGAGGAACCAGGCAGGAGCGACCGUGUACUCUGCCAGGUCACUGCUAGCAGACAGGCCCUCAUCCAAGAGUGGCAGCAGAGUGCAGAGUGCUGCCCAAGGGAGUGGUUUGUUGAAUUUCUUAAUUUGUGUAUUCUACUGACAGUGCCAGCCAUUGGUUUUUAGUAAAUGAGACACUUGCUUCCUAAGAGCUGUCUUUAUAAUCAUAGGUGCCACUGGUCAGGAGGUCUUGUACUACUUCAACCUGCUAUCAGAUAGUCAUUCUGUACAUUCUAAUUCCUGUACCUCUUUGCAUCUGCCAACUUCUUUCCUUCCCCACUGCUUUUGGUUCAGGCCCCCGUUCAUUUCCUUCCUGGAUAUUGUAUAAUACUAGUCUCCUAGCCAGGUCUACAUCGCAGCCAUAUGAGGAUCAAGCUGAUCUUUGUAAACACAGAACUAGCCCUGUCACUUCUCCUUUUCAAAACCUGUGAGUGCCCCCAUCCUUGGCGUUGCAUACUAUCCGGUCAUUUUCUGGGCCAGCCUGCCUUUCCAACCUACUUCCCCCUCCUCUGUUCUUGCACACACCACCUGGCCAUCAGUGCCUAAUUACAGACAUUUCCCCAGGUUCUCUGUAAUCGUUUCUUUCAAUAUUCUAUUCCUCUUUUGGGUCAGCUUCUCUCCCCUGGUCCACUUGGGUACUUCUUUAAAGAAUCACUUCCAGAAAAUUCUUCCUGGCUCAUCCAAACUAUUAAUACUUCCAUCUCUUGUCUGGUGCCCCAGUGGAUCUUUGACACCCUGUGAUGGGCAGCUGUCACACUGUCCUGUAACUGUCGAUAUAUGUUCCUGUGUCCCCUGCCGGAUUCUGACAAGAGGGGAGAGUCCUGUGUCCCCUUCCGGAUUCUGACAAGAGGGGGAAGGCCUCAACCCCUGGCAGUGCACCCAGCGCAGGUCAUUUCUCAGAGCCCAAGCUGUGACCAGUGACGCAGACUGGAAGUCCCGUUUACUGGGAGAGAAGAGGUUAAGGAACACCCAGGUGAACAAUUAGGUCCUCCACAAUGAAGACAGGUAAUGUGGAGGAAAGAGAGCUUGUCAUGGUUCUUGCUCAAGUACCAACUCUAUGGACCCAGGACAGAGCAAGCAAAGAAGAUGGAUCGAUUGAAGAGCCAUCUGACUGUGUGCUUUCUACCUUCUGUGCCCUUUUUAAUCCUAGUAUCCACUCUAGCCACCGCUAAGAGUGUGACUAACAGCACUUUAAAUGGCACUAACGUGGUCUUGGGCUCUGUGCCCGUAAUCAUUGCCAGAACUGACCAUAUCAUAGUCAAGGAAGGGAACAGUGCCUUGAUUAACUGUAGUGUUUAUGGCAUCCCUGACCCACAGUUCAAGUGGUAUAAUUCCAUUGGCAAGCUGCUGAAAGAAGAAGAGGAUGAGAAGGAGAGAGGAGGAGGAAAAUGGCAAAUGCACGACAGCGGCCUCCUGAACAUCACCAAGGUAUCCUUCUCAGACCGAGGUAAAUACACGUGUGUGGCUUCUAACAUCUACGGCACCGUGAACAACACGGUGACCUUGCGCGUCAUCUUCACUUCUGGAGACAUGGGUGUCUACUACAUGGUCGUGUGCCUGGUGGCCUUCACCAUCGUCAUGGUCCUCAAUAUCACCCGCCUGUGCAUGAUGAGCAGCCAUCUAAAGAAGACUGAGAAGGCCAUCAAUGAGUUCUUUAGGACCGAAGGUGCAGAGAAGCUGCAGAAGGCAUUUGAGAUCGCCAAGCGCAUCCCCAUCAUCACCUCCGCCAAAACUCUAGAGCUUGCCAAAGUCACCCAGUUCAAAACCAUGGAGUUCGCCCGCUACAUCGAAGAGCUUGCCAGGAGCGUGCCUCUGCCGCCUCUCAUUAUGAACUGCAGGACUAUCAUGGAGGAGAUUAUGGAGGUGGUUGGGCUGGAGGAGCAGGGGCAGAAUUUUGUGAGGCAUACUCCAGAGGGCCAGGAGGCCGCAGACAGGGAUGAGGUCUACACAAUCCCCAACUCUCUGAAGCGGAGCGACUCCCCUGCCGCUGACUCGGACGCCUCAUCGCUGCACGAGCAACCUCAGCAAAUUGCCAUCAAGGUGUCAGUUCACCCGCAGUCCAAAAAAGAGCAUGCAGAUGACCAAGAGGGUGGACAGUUUGAAGUCAAAGAUGUAGAGGAGACAGAACUGUCGGCGGAACAUUCCCCCGAAACUGCAGAACCUUCUACCGAUGUCACGUCCACCGAGCUAACAUCUGAAGAGCCAACACCUGUUGAGGUACCAGAUAAGGUACUGCCGCCAGCUUACCUGGAAGCCACAGAGCCAGCAGUGACACAUGACAAAAACACCUGCAUUAUUUACGAAAGCCAUGUCUAAUACCAACCCCGAAAAGCUAUGCAUAUCAAGAAAAUCAGGGGCUGCUCCUUGUAAUACAGAUGUAGUACGCACUUGCCGCUAAGCCUUACCAGGAGACUCUCAUCCCUUAGGUAGGAGUGAUGCCACUUUAAAAGGAGAAACACCUGCCUGCAGUGAAUGGGACUGGAAUUUCCCCAGUAGAGAAGGGUGCGAGAAACAUCAGGGUGCAGAAUUGAUACCAGACAGAAGGUGUCUAUGUGAUAAUGAGUUUCAGAGGCUGAUCUCUGCCAAAUACCUUAAUUGGUGAUGCCUUCUUGGCAAAGAGUACACCACUGUAAGAUAUUCUGAGUUCAAGAACCCUGUCCAGUGCCCCCUGCAUUGCUUUUCCUUUUAAAAAGUAUAGGUCUGCUACAAUAGCAAAUGCACGUACGUGGGUUUUUUGCAGUUUCUUCUCAGUUUUAAUUUUGCUUUUCCUUUAUAAUGGGGUCAUUGUUAUUAAUACUAAUUGUUCUUUCUGGUUUAGUCCUCAUUGCCACUUUUGUCCUUAUGUUUCCCUAGAACACGUACCUCAGAGACUUUGGUAUCAGUCACCAGUACCAGGGCUGAUAUCUACAAGUCACAUUACAUUUGUCAUGUUCCAAAGUAGUUACGAGGCUUGUUAUUUUUUUUUCAUUCCCCAGGCCUAUUUCCAUAGAUAGCUUUUUUUGUUUGUUUCCAACGAAGCUGCUGUUAAACGAAACUGAGAAAAACUUUGCCCCGGAAUAGCACUUUAAUAGUCAAAAAUGUGUUUACCUGUCUGAUUGAGUGAGCCUUUUGGUGAGCUCAGCUGAGAUGUAGAGGGAGAUUGUAAAAGGUUAAAUAUACCCACACCACCCAUGAAAGUCACUGUUUAAGUUACAUCAUCCUCCAAAUAAAGACUGAUUCUUUACCUGGAAAAUAUAUUGCUUCCAAAGACAUCAGAUUCAGUGGAUUCCUGUAGGUUAUAGAAUAUUGGCUUCCAAACAGGCUUGCAGGGACCAUAUGCUGUUGGAUGACAUAUAACCAGGUCCACUUUUAUGAACUGCAUAGCUGACUUGGUUGUCCUUAAAGAGGAAAGCGAAAGGUUAGGGUAAUAGCAAAGGGAACUGUGCCAUCAGAUUUUAUGCCAAAACUGUUGAAUAAUUAUGCAGUCCUGCAAGAAAGUGGUUAUAUGUGAGGUGCGUGAUGUUAUGGAAAGAAGACAAAAUUAGUCAUCCAAAGGCUUAAUACCCACUGUGCCAAUAACCAGCUGCCUGGCUUUGGACAAGUCUGGACCUCAGGUCCCUUAUCUGUAGAAGGGGCAGAUGACAUGAGCUCUGAGCACUGUUGAAAUGGUAUCACUGUCACACAGAACCAAACCAAUAUUCACAUCCUUGCUCCUUUUCACAAUGACUUUAAAGAUUUUUGCUUUCAUCUCUUGGUCCACCUAACAUUUUCAUGCUUCAUUACUUAAAUAAGAAUGUUGGUUUUGAGAAAUAGCAUUUUAAACAAAUUGUGGAUCUUCUCCUUCCAAAAAAACCAUUAGGACCACAUCUGCAAUUAAGAUUUAAUAUUGGUGAGAAUGAGUGGUUUUAUUUAAUUUUCCCUUAAAAGCAAAGGAGACAGUAAUCUUAAUAAAUUCAUAGGGGCCGUGGCCACAUCAGGUAAUGGGGUUAUGAUGUCCAAGAUUGCAUGGAUCACAUUGGUGAUGAGAGCAGACCCAGAUGUUUAGUCCUCACUCUGUCACCAUCUGAGGAGGUGACCUUGGACAACUCCCUUCCUCUCUCUGGGAUUUAAUCUUUUUCAUCUGUAAAAUAUGCAGGUAGUACUCGAGGGUCUACAGGAUCCCUUCUAGUUGAAACAUUUAUAGUUCACAGAAAGUUUGCAGUCUUCCAGGAUAACCAACCCCCGUUGCAUGAGACAAGCAAAAAAUGGGUCCAUGAAAUUGGAUACUUUUGCCAUCCAAACUUUACAACAAACAUUAUCUGGCUCUGUAAUUGAGAGCAGUGGGCUUGGUUUUAAACCUAGCCUUGAUUAGUUUGUUUAUAGAUAACUGUUGUGGAAGGUGAUAGAACUAGUCAUGGAGUUUGAUGAGACAUCUCUUGAAAAGGACUGAACUGUUGACUUCUGGUUAGAAGUGCUUUGGGCAGUCACAUAAAGAAAUGAGCAGUGAGAAAUCAGGAGAAAUUAUGACUCCUGUUGGGCUUUCUGGACUAGCAUUGUAUGUUUUUGGGUUGCAGAAAAGUUUUAACACCACCUCUUAGAAUAUAAAAAUUUUCCAGUUGUCAUGGAGGUCCACAGAUUCAUUACCAUGGGUUUAUAUGCCCAAAGCAACAACAGAGGACUUAAGUUCAUUUUGUGAUACUGUAUGGAUGUUACCCCAUCCUAUUCAGUUGUCAUUCCACCCAAACCCAUGUGUAGGUUUCCACAUGGAAAGGAGAAGGCAUCCAUUCCACCUAGACAUUGAAUAGUGAUAAUAAGCUAAAAGUGGGCAGAUUUUCAGUGGAGCAAGAGCAGAAAUAUGCGGCCAAAGAAUGUUUCCUGAUUGGUUUUGCUGCUUUAGACUGCAGUGGGGAGAGCUUAUGUAGAUUUUCAAAACUUUCUCCCUCUUUAAGGCAUCAUAAUGCUCUCGGUUUUGAUAACAACUGACAUAAAGGGAGGUUGACUUAAAAUGGGAAUUUCUCCUUCCAAAAAUGCUACACUCUUCCUAUCCAUCCUACAGCUUCUUUAUGAAAUGAGAGGCCCUCCUGCUAGAAUAUGAAAUGCAGAAGACCUCAUGACUUUCAGCUGAUUUUUCAAAGAUAAAGUGAACUGUUCAGCUUCAUAGAAAUUCAUGCGAGUGUGACUGAACGUGUGUGCAUACACACUCGUGCACAUUGGACUCAUUUGGGCAGUUUUAAAAGCUUCACACUAAAUCCAAAGCCUCGUCCUUUGGGUCGUAUGUAGUCGUUUGUAAAAUCAAUUUCUGGCUUCUGAGUCAUCCUGGUCAUAUCUCUAGCAAUGUUUUUCUUGAAAUUCUGAAAAUGAUUCACAUAUGUGUGUACAUUUAAUUCACUUAGAUGAUCUGUAAACUUGGAUGGUAUUUAUUCUAAAUGGGGAAAACAAUUUUAUAUGGAAAAAUCUAUGUAAUUUAUAAUGGUUUUGUUUUAUAUAUUAUAUUUUCAUAUCUCUAGGGCACAUCUAUCCUCAUCUUUUUGUAUACCAUACUUAGCAAAAAGAAAUACUAAUACUUGACUAAAAUCUCUAGGAACCAAACGUGAUACAUGUGAUAUAUAGCUUCUAGAAAUCGCUCUAAAAAUCUCUGAAUGUCUCAUCCAUCCCAAGCAUUAUUGUGCUGUGUCAUUAUGUCCAGAAUGAUUUGUCUUGGAUGCUUAUGAGCAUUUGUUUUUCACAACUAAGGUUGAAAGACCUGACAUCUCACACAAUGGGGUUCUGGAAUUCCCCUUUCCUCCUUUAUCUGUUUUUAUUGUUUGUUUCAUUUUUAAUUGCACCAGUCUAUGUUGUCGAAACUUUGUUUUGAAGGGCAAAUGUGAGAUAACAAGAAAGCAAUGUGAUGGAAAGACUGGAUGAAUUUACCUAUGGCUAUGUAAAUUAUUUUAAUGGACUGAUAAGAUGUUUCAAGUCUCAUGCUUGGAUCUUUAUUUAUUGGUGAUCUAGGAUCUGCUCAGCUCUUUAGCACAUGAAGAAAAUCAGGUACAAAGGACAUUUGCAUGUUUGGAACAGCAUGCUCUAAGCCCCGUGCAGCCAACACAAAUUAACUUGACUGUAGAAACACCAAUUCCAGCUGCUGGAAGAAAUGGUUUAGAAAGGCAAACCAGAUACCUUUUAUUCUGCCCUAGGAAAUACAGUGUUGAUCAGUGCUAAAACUCUUCAGUGGCAGUCACUGUGGUUCUUUUAACUGGGGAUUUCCUUUCAGUGUUUCAUUUGGUACCAAAACAGAACAUUUACCUUACAUUUCAGAUACUCUGUUUUCUCAGCAUUGUUCAGAUACUUUCCUUUACCGCUCUUCACGUACCCUUUUGGCAUUGAGUAAUUCUAUAAAUGUUUCUAUCCUUGGUUUUUAAACCAAGUUAUUCAUACUCUUAAAAUAUCUACCAAAUCUCAUUGUAUUUUCACAUAUUUUGAGCAUCAAGAUACUGGUCAUUUUAAAAAAUCCUUCAGUAAAUAGCACAGUUUAUUUUCCUAAUGACAUUUUUAGGGUUUCUUCAUUGAUCAACCAGGUUUGGGUUACACAAAUCAAUUGUGGGGGAAAAAUCAAAUAAAACAAUUGCUUAUUAUAUUUUCCAAAGGACUGAGCAUUUAUCUUUUAUUCACGAAGAUAUCAUAUGAGGAUGAUAAUGAUCUUUAACAGAUUUUUUAGAGAUAGAAUUUAUAAAGAGGCUGAUACUAAGAAUACUACAAUCAAAAUUGAAGCUAGAGAAUGUAAAAAUAGAAAGUAAAUAGUUCUAAGAAUAUUCUGGCAUAAAUUAUUUUUAUUUAGCCAAUAAAAUAGCCUCCAAAUGUAUAUCUCAGACACCAUAGAGCUGCUAACAAUGAGAAUCAAGGAAGAUGCUUGCACUUAGAUUUCGUUUGUUGUAUUUCAGUAGUUCUGGAUGUCCUUUGUUAAAAUUGGAAAAUGGAAAAAUGUCUCGACAGAAAUGUCAAUCUGGUGAUUCUGUGAACUGUAAAAUGUUCACUUUUAAAAAUAAAGUUGUAAACAAGUUACUCAUAUAAGUUGGUAUUACAGUAGCAAAAACAGAAAACCAUGUGAUCCAUCCUGUAUUUUGAUUGAUGCUUUAAUAAAGGGUUUGCACAGCUGUG